GUAGUAGCCUGAGGUUCCCUUAUGUGGCCCUAUAGCUGUUACUGAAGGAAGUAGCCUACGUCCACGCCUACAACUGAAGUCUCUUGACAAACACCUCACCCCUGCCUCCGGGAUGAAAGGGGGUAACCUAGACCUGAAUGGGCUUGACCAUCUCACAACUGCUCGCGUGACGACCGCAUUCGUGGCAGGUAAGAAGAUUGCUGUAUCAACUCAAGAAAGCAGUAACUUCACUGUCUUUGUAUUUUGAAUUGCAACAACAACUUUGAUAUCAACAAUGAAGCAAUGAUAUCUAAGAACAAAAGAGUAUUUGCCAACAGUCAUCAUAAUAUCAAGUGAUUGUAUAAGCAGAAACAAGCUGUCACAGACCUGUGCGUCAGCUAAUAUAUGGAGAAUGCUUUCUUCUGAUACUAUUUACUUAGAGGCAGUUUUAAUAUAAAUCAUUUCAAUUAUAUCUACAUCAAAUAAAAUAAAAAUGAGUGAAGCCCCCAGAUUCUUCGUUGGACCAGAAGAUACAGAAAUAAAUCCUGGAAAUUAUCGACAUUUCUUCCACCAUGCAGAUGAAGACGAUGAGGAGGAAGAUGAUUCUCCACCAGAAAGGCAGAUUGUGGUUGGAAUAUGUUCCAUGGCAAAGAAAUCCAAAUCCAAACCAAUGAAGGAAAUUCUUGAACGGAUCUCCUUAUUUAAAUAUAUCACAGUAGUAGUAUUUGAAGAGGAGGUUAUUUUGAAUGAACCAGUGGAAAACUGGCCUUUAUGUGAUUGUCUUAUUUCUUUCCAUUCUAAAGGAUUUCCACUGGACAAAGCGGUUGCCUAUGCAAAACUCAGGAAUCCAUUUGUAAUCAAUGACUUGAAUAUGCAGUAUCUCAUACAAGAUAGGAGAGAAGUAUAUAGUAUUCUUCAAGCUGAAGGUAUUUUACUUCCUCGUUAUGCUAUUUUGAACCGUGACCCAAAUAAUCCCAAAGAAUGUAAUCUGAUUGAAGGGGAAGAUCAUGUAGAAGUAAAUGGGGAAGUUUUUCAAAAGCCAUUUGUAGAAAAGCCAGUCAGUGCAGAAGAUCACAAUGUUUACAUUUAUUACCCAACUUCUGCUGGUGGUGGAAGUCAAAGACUCUUUAGAAAGAUUGGCAGUAGAAGUAGUGUUUAUUCUCCAGAAAGCAAUGUACGAAAAACAGGCUCAUAUAUAUAUGAAGAGUUUAUGCCCACAGAUGGUACUGAUGUUAAGGUUUAUACAGUGGGUCCAGAUUAUGCCCAUGCUGAAGCUCGAAAAUCUCCAGCACUUGAUGGCAAGGUGGAACGAGACAGUGAAGGAAAAGAAGUAAGAUACCCUGUUAUUCUCAAUGCACGAGAGAAAUUAAUUGCUUGGAAAGUCUGCCUUGCUUUUAAGCAAACAGUUUGUGGCUUUGAUUUGUUACGGGCCAAUGGACAGUCCUAUGUCUGUGAUGUCAAUGGCUUCAGUUUUGUGAAAAAUUCCAUGAAGUAUUAUGAUGACUGUGCAAAAAUACUUGGAAAUAUUGUAAUGCGAGAACUUGCUCCACAAUUUCAUAUUCCAUGGUCAAUACCCUUAGAAGCUGAAGAUAUCCCAAUUGUACCAACUACAUCUGGAACUAUGAUGGAACUUAGAUGUGUCAUAGCUGUUAUACGUCAUGGGGAUCGAACACCAAAACAAAAAAUGAAAAUGGAAGUGAGACAUCAGAAAUUUUUUGAUCUUUUUGAAAAGUGUGAUGGAUAUAAAUCAGGGAAAUUAAAACUCAAAAAACCAAAACAGUUACAGGAAGUGCUAGAUAUUGCACGACAGCUUCUUAUGGAGCUAGGGCAAAAUAAUGAUUCUGAAAUUGAAGAAAACAAGCCAAAACUUGAACAACUUAAGACUGUAUUAGAGAUGUAUGGUCAUUUUUCUGGAAUAAAUCGUAAGGUUCAGUUGACCUAUCUCCCUCAUGGUUGUCCUAAAACAUCUAGUGAAGAGGAGGACAGCCGAAGAGAAGAACCAUCUUUACUUUUGGUUCUAAAAUGGGGAGGUGAAUUAACUCCUGCAGGCAGGGUCCAGGCUGAAGAACUUGGAAGAGCCUUCAGGUGUAUGUAUCCUGGAGGUCAAGGAGAUUAUGCAGGAUUUCCUGGUUGUGGUUUACUUAGAUUACAUAGCACCUACAGACAUGACCUCAAAAUAUAUGCCUCUGAUGAAGGACGAGUCCAGAUGACUGCAGCUGCUUUUGCAAAGGGGCUUUUAGCUUUGGAAGGAGAGCUUACACCCAUUCUUGUUCAAAUGGUGAAAAGUGCAAAUAUGAACGGUCUUUUGGAUAGUGAUAGUGACUCUCUGAGCAGUUGUCAGCAACGUGUGAAGGCAAGGCUUCAUGAAAUACUUCAGAAAGACAGAGAUUUUACUGCUGAAGAUUAUGAAAAGCUUACUCCAUCUGGAAGCAUUUCUCUUAUCAAAUCAAUGCAUUUAAUUAAAAACCCUGUGAAGACCUGUGAUAAAGUUUAUUCCUUAAUUCAGAGUUUGACUUCUCAAAUCAGACAUCGAAUGGAAGAUCCUAAAUCAUCAGAUAUUCAGCUUUACCAUAGUGAAACAUUGGAGCUUAUGCUACGUAGAUGGUCCAAGUUAGAGAAAGACUUUAAAACAAAGAAUGGAAGAUAUGAUAUUAGUAAAAUCCCUGACAUAUAUGACUGUAUAAAAUAUGAUGUCCAGCAUAAUGGUUCCUUGAAAUUAGAAAACACAAUGGAAUUAUAUAGGCUUUCGAAGGCAUUAGCAGAUAUUGUUAUCCCUCAGGAAUAUGGUAUAACUAAAGCUGAAAAACUGGAGAUUGCCAAAGGCUACUGUACUCCUCUGGUUAGAAAAAUUCGCUCAGACCUUCAGAGGACACAAGAUGAUGACACUGUAAAUAAACUUCAUCCUGUGUAUUCUAGAGGUGUUCUGUCUCCUGAACGUCAUGUUCGUACUAGAUUAUAUUUUACCAGUGAAAGUCAUGUACAUUCUUUGCUGUCUAUUCUUCGCUAUGGUGCCUUAUGCAAUACCAAUGAUUCUCAGAAUGAAGAUGGAGGAAUGGUGAAGGAGAUGGAAUCAAAGGAUGAACAGUGGAAACGAGCUAUGGAUUAUUUAAACGUUGUCAAUGAGCUCAACUACAUGACUCAGAUUGUUAUCAUGCUUUAUGAGGAUCCUAAUAAGGAUCUUUCCUCAGAAGAACGCUUUCAUGUUGAAUUACACUUUAGUCCGGGAGCCAAAGGUUGUGAAGAAGACAAAAAUUUGCCAUCUGGCUAUGGAUAUAGACCAGCUUCCAGAGAGAAUGAAGGCAGGAGACCUUUUAAAAUUGAUAAUGAUGAUGAACCACAUACUUCUAAAAGAGAUGAAGUUGAUCGAGCUGUGAUAUUGUUUAAACCAAUGGUAUCAGAGCCAAUUCAUAUACACAGGAAGUCUCCACUUCCAAGAUCUAGGAAGACGGCUACAAAUGAUGAAGAGAGCCCCCUGAGUGUGUCUAGCCCAGAGGGUACUGGUACCUGGCUGCAUUAUACCAGUGGUGUGGGUACUGGGCGUCGAAGACGCAGAUCAGGGGAACAAAUCACUUCUUCCCCUGUCUCCCCCAAAUCAUUGGCUUUCACAUCCAGUAUUUUUGGCUCAUGGCAACAGGUUGUAUCUGAAAAUGCUAAUUACCUGAGAACACCAAGAACUCUUGUGGAACAGAAGCAGAAUCCUACUGUAGGGUCUCACUGUGCGGGCCUGUUUAGCACCUCGGUGCUCGGGGGUUCUUCAAGCGCACCUAACCUACAGGAUUAUGCUCGUACUCAUCGUAAAAAGCUGACCUCUUCUGGCUGCAUAGAUGACGCCACACGCGGUUCUGCUGUUAAAAGGUUUUCUAUCUCAUUUGCUCGACACCCAACCAAUGAACACCUACACCUCUAUAGGUGCUGGUCCGUUUCCUCUGUGGAAUUUCUAGGCUCCAGUGGCUUUGAAUUGUAUUCCAUGGUGCCAUCUAUUUGUCCUCUAGAAACUCUUCAUAAUGCCCUAUCUUUAAAGCAAGUGGAUGAAUUUCUUGCUUCCAUUGCUUCUCCAUCAUCUGACGUUCCACGGAAGACCGCUGAAAUUUCCUCUACAGCUUUACGUUCCAGUCCAAUAAUGAGAAAAAAAGUAUCUUUAAAUACGUAUACACCUGCAAAGAUCCUCCCAACACCACCAGCUACCUUAAAGAGCACUAAAGCAAGCAGCAAACCAGCUACAAGUGGACCUUCUAGUGCAGUUGUUCCUAAUACCUCAUCUCGGAAAAAGAAUAUAACUAGCAAAACAGAAACGCAUGAACACAAAAAAAACACUGGGAAAAAGAAAUGAAAUCUUAGCAGAAGCUGGAACUUUUUAUACUUAUAAAAAUAGUAUGUUCUUAUGUUUCUCCUUAUGCAUUUAUGUGUUCACUUAAAAAUGUUUUUAAAUCUAAGGUUUUCUUUGUUUAUGUUCAGGUAAGGAACUGUUGUCAUGAUCUGGAAAUGUUUAAAACAAUGUUUGUUAGCAUUCUGUGAGCAGCAAAACUUAUAGUGAUAAAAAUCGAUUGUUGUUAAUAUGAUGUUUACCAUGUGCACAUAGUAAUGAAAAGGAACAUAAAAGCCCAGCAGGCUCGUACCAAAGUCACAGCAGUAAUGCUAUGUACUGCAGAGUCUGAUGAGCUGGCCUUUGUGCACACUUUUAUUUUCAUGGGAUUGCAUCUUAGCUGUUAAAACUUCUAGAUUGAAAUUUGACAGCCAGGGUUACAUAUUGGGGACUUUUAAAGUGUCUUUCCAAAGAGAUUUCAUUAACCGUUUAGAUUAGAAUAUCUUUCCCAAUUGUUACAGUGACAUAUAUGCUGCAAUAUUUAACAACUGGAGUAUUAGCCACAUGGGUUAUUUUUUCAAUCUGUGUUUUGAAUUUUUUUAUUGUGUGUUAUUUAAAAUAUUACAUAUGCAGCUGGGAGAACUACACCUUUGUGCACAUAGAUUUAUAUAUUAAUUUGUAGAAAAUAUUUUCUUUAUAUAUUUCCUUACCAUACAAGGUGCCUUGUUCAUCAGGAAAACUUUUGUUUUGUAUUUUGACAAGAAAGGCACCUUCAGAGUUUCUUUUUAAGUAUAGUUGACAAGUGUAUAAAUGUUACACUUACUUUCAGAGUUCUUUUUAGAUCUAAAGAAGUCAGUUCAAAAAUGGAAAUCAACAAUGUUAGGAGAAAUCUGAAUUCUGUUAAGUUAGUAAGUAUUAUGUAUAGCAUCUGUUUUUAACCAUUUCCAUUCUUAUCCCUAGUGUAUCAGUUGAUCACACUAAGAAAGCUUAAAGAUUGAGCAUUUGAAAUAAAUGCUCUUUAUAAAUGAUUAGAUUUUUGAAGGGAUAUUGAAAUCAUUGCGCUGUGAUUUCAUCUGUGAUGUGAAAAAUCAAUUUAUUAUCCUUGGUGCUUUCCCCCCCACCAAUGCACAAAUAAUUGUGAACAGCUUGAAAUGACUUAAACUGUAAUCCAAAUGGGACAAUCUGAUAAGAAUUUCAUGCAUUGGUAGUUAAAUAACUUAAAUUGCUAAAGCUUUAGCUUGAAAUUUAUGUUUAGAAAAACUAUUGAUUUCCCAUGGUAUGAAUAUAACUAUUGUAAUUCUUCAAAUGAGACUCUUCUCACCUUAAAUAGUCAUAUAUUAAUUAACUUAUAGGAAAUAAGCAUACUAUAUGUUAGCUGUUUUAAAAGGUACCAGAUGUAAGAGUCAUAAAUAUAUGCAAUUAAAGAAGUUCAUAGAUUUCACAUGAAUGUAAAUGUGUUAUAUGGAGACAUGUCUUGUAAACAGUUGAAUGUAUGUAAGUUUUCUGUUUGUGAAAAUGUAGUUAAUGUACUCACUGUGGAGGUCAUAAGGAAGCUACUUUUUUUUUAAAGUGGAACCUAAUUAAAAUAUUUCCAGAAUCAAAGAGACUUAAAUGGUAAAUUUUUAAAAUUUUCUUAUCUCUUACUUUUUAGUUUUCAAAGUAGAAAAAAUCAGGAAUUUUUUUAUUAACUAGUACUUACAUAUUAAAUAAAAUUUAUUAUUGGCUAUAUACAUAGCAAUAUAUUACUUUCCAAACUAGAAAGUACAGUACAACUAACUUUUUCCAUUGUUAUGCAAGAACUAUUACUUUCCUGUAGUCACCAAACUCAGUAGUAUUGCUCUGUAGACUAGACACUCUAUUUGUAAAAAUCUUAGAAUCACUUUCCAAAACAAAUAAAAAGUCUACUGUAUCAGAGCAAAAUGUUAUAGUUAUCACUGUUUAGUGGCAGUUUGACUGAAGCAUCUGUUUCUCACUUGAUUCUGUCCUGAGAAGAUGUGGGAUUUUUUGGUUUUAAAUACUAGAAGAUAUUUCUUCUUAGAGCCCAGUCCUCCAUCCCAAAGAGGUGAACUAGCCCAGCAUGAAGAAUUGUCUAGUCACCCUGAGAUAUUAAUCUUCAUAAUGUAUUAUUCAGUUCCUUCACCCUUAAAAGCCAUAUAAUAGGCUCAGACCUAACUUAGCCCUUGAAGUCUAGUGCUGGCAGAUUCUGCUGCCCUGGUUUAAAUGAGUUACGUAGUCCAUUCUCAAAUACUAGCAAAUUUGGGGGGCGUGGUACAGCAAUUUUGGGUGAAGAAAAGUGUGCUGAACACCUUAUGUCAGUGAUAGACAAGAUAUAGAGGCUGAAGGGAAUACAGUAAAGUAACAAAAACAUGUGGCAGUGUGCUUAGCAUAAACAUAGAGCACAAAGGCAAUAGAUGGAAAUUAUGAGAGAAAAGUUAAAGUUCUUCAAGAAAUAUCCAAUUAAAACUCACUAGCCAAGGAAAAAGUUUCUGUUUUCACCCGGAUUUCUUUUUGGGUUGACUCUGUCUGACCUAAAUGUCCACUGUUAACUAGUGCCAUGCCAGUUUGAACCAAGAUUUCACAUUUUUGUUUUGUAUUCAUACUUUGGUAGAAAUUUCUCAGUCUUUGUGUAUUUAUAAGAAUUUGCUUUACACAUAGUGUACAGUGUUUAUUAACUUUACAUCAUUUUAUCCUUGCCUUACUAUCUGGACAGUGUAGACUGCCUAUAUUCUUAGUUGGGGUUGGGAUCUCUUCUCUUAGAGUGGCCCAGCAGUUUUAGCCCCUCUCUAAUUCUCUUUUCCUGUGUUGGGAGAUAUCAAAACAACAGAAUUCUUGCCAGUGGGAACAUUUUUCUUUUUUAGACAAGGUCUCAUUCUGUCACCCCAGCUGGAGUGCAGUGGCACAGUCUUAAUUCACUACAGCCUUGAACUCCUGGGCUCAAGAAAUCUUUCUGCUUCAGCCUCCUAAAUAGCUGGUACUAUAGGUGCGUGCCACCACACCCAGCUCAUGGGAAUAAUUUUUACACUCCUUCAGAAGGAGUCAUUUGUGAUUGGAGUCCACAUAGAAACAGGUUUCCCUCUGUACAUAAUCGUAGGUACCAAAAUAUUACUGUGUAAAGUGUUGUUUAUAUAGGUCAAUUUUUGUGGAAGAUCUAAUUUCUAUUUUCAGAGAACAGAGCACAUUAAAAAAUCUAUUUAGUAUUGUGUACUAUAUAAUCUAUGUGAAUUAUAGCUCCUUAACUAAAUAUAUUACUGAGUUUUUUUUUUAAUACUGUAAGUUCUAGGGUACAUGUGCACAAUGUGCAGGUUUGUUACAUAGGUAUACAUGUGCCAUGUUGGUUUGCUGCACCCAUGAACUCAUCAUUUACAUUAGGUAUUUCUCCUAAUGCUAUCCCUCCCCCAGCCCCCCACCCACUGACAGGCCCAGUGUGUGAUGUUCCCCGCCCUGUGUCCAAGUACUGUUCUCAUUGUUCAGUUCCCUCUUAUGAGUGAGAACAUGCGGUGUUUGGUUUUCUGUCCUUGUGAUAGUUUGCUGAGAAUGAUGGUUUCCAGCUUCAUCCAUGUCCUUGUCAUCCUUUUUUUUGGCUGCAUAGUAUUCCAUGGUGUAUAUGUGCCACAUUUUCUUAAUCCAGUCUAUCAUUGAUGGACAUCUGGGUUGGUCCCAAGUCUUUGCUAUUGUGAAUAGUGCCACAAUAAACAUACGUGUGCAUGUGUCUUUAUAGUGGCAUGAUUUAUAAUCCUUUGGGUAUAUACCCAGUAAUGGGAUGGCUGGGUCAAAUGGUAUUUCUAGUUCUAGAUCCUUGAGGAAUCGCCACACUGUCUUCCACAAUGGUUGAACUAAUUUACACUCCCACCAAGUGUUCCUAUUUCUCCACAUCCUCUCCAGCAUCUGUUGUUUCCUGACUUUUCAAUGAUCGCCAUUCUAACUGGCGUGAGAUGGUAUCUCAUUUGUAAGAUGAUAUCUCAUUGAGAUUUUUAUAAACUGCUUUUCUUUUGGUUCAUGUGCUUUGUCAUGGAUUGUGAGAAAAACAUCUUUUCGCUUAGGGAUCACUGUCAAUUUCUCCUUUUAUUAUCAAUGGUUUUUACUUUACUUUUUAUAUAGUAUGUGGGUAUGUUUUCUGGUGCAUAUAAAUUCAUGAAUGCUAGAUUUUCAUUAUAGGUUUUACCUUAUCAUUAUUAAAAUGUCCUUUUUGUCCAUUGGAUACUUUUUGUUCUAUAAAUUGUCAGAUAUUAAGAUUAUGACCUAUGCUUUAUUUUGGCUUGCAUUUGCCUGAUAUUCAUCUUUUUACUUUUUGGUAUUUGUGUCACUUUGUUUUAGGUUAUUUAAUAUAGUAUAUAUUGGGUUUUGCUUUGUGAUUCAAUUUUAAGAUCCCUUUUACUUAAUAGAUUAGUGUAGUCUGUUUUAUGUAAUGUAUCUUUGCUUUUAGAUUGUGCUUGCUUUUUUUAUUGCUUUAAAAUUCUUUUGUCUUUCUGUAACAAUACUUUCCACUGCAAGUAGGAAAAUUCCAAUUGAAACUGGUUUAAAUCAUCAGAAAAUGUAUUAUUACACAUUUCUGAAGGUCCAAAGGUGGGGUUGGCUUCAGCCACAGUUGCAUUAGCCAUAUUGUCAUCAAAAGCCCAAGUGACCUCCCUUGUCACCUCUGGCAUAGUAUAAACUUUAUCCCAAAGUUGUUUUCUCUCGUGUUAACAAUAAUUGCUGUCGGUUUCAGUGAGGACUACAUAUUUUUUUUGUUCAUGUCCAACACAAUAAAAAUUGAGGGAAGUUCUGUCCCAAUCCUGGAAUAUUAAUAUUAAGCCAUCUACUUCAGUGUGAUUGAGCCAACUUCUUUGAUCAUCUACUCACCCCUAGAUAAAUAGAAUACUCCAGGAGAUUCCCAUGACCUUACUGACCCUAGAGCAGAUGAUGGAGUCAGUUUUUCCGAAAAGCCUCAGCACUGUUGACAUUUUGGACCAUAAAAUUCUACAUCAUAGGAAGCUGUUCCAUGCAUAGCAGCAUGUCUAGUAGGAUCUCUGUACCUAGCUGUGAAGUGUUGAGAGUCAGUUAAGGUAAGUAGCUGAAAUGAAAAUAACAAUCACAUCUUUAUUCACUUACUAUGAUAAAAUUAUAAGCAAGAGACCAAAAAGGAAAGUAGGGCCAGCUCCUUGUUGUUCCAUUUUUCCCCUACCAUGGACUAGCACUGGACAUGCGUCAAUCAGACGACAUGCAGUCCAGGCAGAGGAAAUUGUUUCACUGCUAAGGAGCAAUGAACAAAAGGUUCCUGCCAUCUUAUGGACCUCAAGGACUGCGGACAGGGAGCAGGGAAGGGUUAGAAGUAGAAAACAACUGAGUCAGAGUGGAGAUGAGUGUCUCAGUCAAGGCCCACCAAUAGCGAGGUCUCUGUGGAGGCACCUGAAAAGUGUCUCAACCAAGGCCCCCUGAUAAGGAAGACUCAGCAUGGAGGUACCUGGUCUAGGAAUGCAGCUAGGUUUAUAGACAUGGCCAGCCCAGGGGGUCCUGAGCACCAGAUACAACUCCCUCCAGAGACUGGCUGUGUUUAAAUCUCAUGUGGGAAGGGCACCUUUCCCCUACAAAGCCUGUCAGGCAAAGCCUUUGUAAUUGCUUAUGGUCAGGCCUGAAAGAUCACACAUCAGACUUUGGCCUGGAACAUAUCUCCUCACCCUAAAUGCCAGCAGCAUCGCCUCCAAACUGUGGCAGUCAAAAAUGUCUCCAGACAUUAGUAAAUGUCUUUUGUGAGGGAAGAAUUGACCCUAGUUAAGAACCACUGCCCUAAAGCACAUGAUUCUGUGGAAAAGAAGGAUAUAUGACCAAAAUCAUCAUUUUGGAUAGUGAGGGCAUGGAUAAUGGAUACAUAAUCAGCAAUGUAUGCUGUAUACUACACUUGCAUUAUGUUAUUCACAUUUGCUAUAGUUCACUUGUUGUGCUAAUGGUUUUUUCCUUCACUAUGAUUUUGAAUUAUAUUUAAUUUUAAAGUCUAUAUAUAUAUAUAUAUAGAUCCUAUCUGUUGACUCCUUGCUGUGAACAAUAUCCAAUUAGUGUAUUUUUUCCUCUACUGCACAGUUUUGGUUGAUUAUUUUUUCCUUUUCAUUUCUUUUCUGAACUUUGUUAGCUUAUGUUGCAUUUCCUUUGGUUGUUUUGCUAUGGUGUUUCUGAUCAACUACAUUUCUUUAUGAACUCUAUUUCCUUAAGUUCUUUGAGUUAUGACAGUAUAUUUGGUCACAUUUUUCAUGUGCUCAGCUGAUUCAUUCUUUCCUGUUGAGUGGUUUUUAUCUGCUAAUUGUUUCUGCUUGUUCCAUUUCUCCUUUUCUUGAAGUGUUUGUGCAUGAACACUGUGCAGGUUUAUUUUCAAGUAUUACUUACCUUUAUAUGAGAUAAAUUUCUUUCUGGCUCAUCUAUUUGAUACAAUUUCUUUUUUGUUUGUUUUUGUUUUGUUUUUGUUGUUUUUUAAAAUGCAAUUUCAUAUGUUAGGUAGGUUGGCUUUUCUUUUUCUUUUUCUUUUUUUUUUUGAGAUGGAGUUUUACUCUUGUUGCCUAGGCUGGAGUGCAGUGGCAUGAUCUCAGCUCACUGCAACCUCCACCUUCCAGUUUCAAAUGAUUCUCCUCCCUCAGCCUCCAGAGUAGCUGGGAUUACAGGCGCCCGCCACCACGCCUGGCUAAUUUUUGCAUUUUUAGUAGAGACUGGGUUUCACCAUGUUGGCCAGGCUGGUCUCGAACUCCUGACCUCAUGAUCUUCCUGCCUCAGCCUCCCAAAAUGCUGGAAUUACAGGCAUGAGCCAUCAUGCCCGGCCGUAGGUUGGCAUUUUAAGCUCACACAAUCCUACCAAGGUGACAGUGAAUCUCCUUAUGACAGGAUUGUGGGUCUGAGAGAGCUGUUGUAGCCUUUUACUCUCUCCAGUCAACAAAGAUUGGCAACUACAGGGUUACCACCUUUGGAGUCUCUUUCCUCCUGUCUGCCACGUCUACAGACUACUGCUUGUCAAUGUGAUAUGCAUGUAUUUUCUUCUUCAGCUUUGCCCCUCCUGCCACUGUACCAGACAAUAUCCAGGAAAUCCCCUACUACUGACACUCAUCCCAUUUCCAUUGUUUUAGAGAAGGAACUAGUUGUUGUUGUUUUUUUUUCCCUGUCUCAGAUUAUGUCAUCUAUUUUGGAGUAUUUUGGUCUAAUGACUUUGGCUGCGAUAUGGAGCUAUCUGACCUUUACUGCACCUGGCAGCUCUAUCUCCUAUUUUGGGGUUGAGGUUAAAGUGUCUUCUAGUUUUGUUGAAGAUAGUUUAUGUUUCUCUUCAUAUUUGAUGAUAAUUUUUUAAAUUAAGACCUAAUUUCUCCUUCAUUUUCAAACUGGAUAUCAUUUCUUUUGUGGUUAAUAUUCUUUGACAAGAAGGAAGAGGAGGAGGAAGAAGAACAAAAGAAGCCUGCCUCUCUUUAGACUGCCCAUCUCAAUUAUAUUUUAAAAAUGAAGUUAAUAUCUGUCCUGCUAACAGUAGUGUUGUCAGAAUCAAAUGAAAUAAUAUUUGGUAAACUAUAAAGUGAAGACCAAAUUUGAAGGACUAUUUGUUUUUGUUGUAAUAGAGUUGUAUAUAGUCCAGAUGUCAACCAGGCCUCUUCAGCAUUUUUAUAGUCAAAGAUGUACAAGAUAGCUCCUAAUGCUCUUUUAUGGCUGCUCCUGUUGCCAGGGCAACAGCCUGCCUAGUAACAAUCUAACAGACACCCCCCAAAAACCAAAAAAUAAAGGUUAUUCUAGCAUCUUCUCCUUUUAAAAAUCUUUAAAAUAAGAGAAUUCAGUUCUUCCCAAAGCAGUGUUUAAAAAAAAAAAGUAUUUAAAUAAAAUCAAGGAUACCAUCCCACCCACCUAUCUUACAUUUUGUGUGGUAUGAGUGGCACCAUUGUGUGACCCAGGUAGGAUAGUGGAUGUACAGUUUAGAUACCCAUUUUAAAGCAGUUAGAAAGAUGUAACUUGACAAGGAAAGCAGUCUCUUUUGUCAUUCUACAUUUAGUGCUUCAGGAGUACUUGAUAUAUGGAAGGAUUUUUUUAAAAAAAAGGAAAAAUGAAUAUGCCUUCAGAAAGUUUUUUGCUGCUUUUAAAAGCCAUAGAUUUGUCUUAAGUUAGUCAAUGCUGAAUAGAAAGCUUGAUGAUAAAGGUGGGUGGGUGGAUGGAUGGAUGGAUGAAUGAAGGAAAAAUUAGGAGAAAAGAGAAAGCAGAGGAGGGGUGAGACAGAGAACAAAAGAACACAGGCUCUACUGUUAACAAAAAGCAGCAUCGCUGAUGUGUGGGGAAUAAAUUGGAAGUCAUAUCAUUACGACUUUUUUUUCAUGCCACAUAGAUAUGCUGAUUUGUCCAACAAUGCCUGUACUCAAAAGUCAUGACAAUAAAAUGAGACCUGGGAGUCCCAAAUGUUAUUAACUACCACAAUUUUAUAUAACUGAUUCUUCACUGGUCAUCCAGAAGCCUUUUUGAAAGUCCCACUGCCAUACCUGCCUCCUCGGUGAAAUAGAUGUAAAAGCCACAAAGAGAGAAUCAAUGAGCCACACUCAUAUUGGAAGCGAAUGGAGUUGACUUCACCAGUGGGAAAAGCAAUUACUUUUCAAAGUGAAAACUGAUCAAUUCACAACUCAAGGAAAGCAUGGAGUAAUUUCAGAACUCCAGUAAGAAGUGAUAAAUGUCUAGUUUGGAAUCAUGUGGCUGAAAAUCUUACCAUAUGCUUUCCACAGGCUGAGCAAGAGGAUAGAUCAUUGAAUAGAUGCUUUAAUUCCAUUUUUGACAAUGAACCUUGUGCUUCUGAAAAUAUUUAUAUUUAACCAUGAGGUUAUGAUGAUUUUUUCUCUACACUUUUUGAGAAGCCUCUUCAGAAAAGAGCAAAGUUGUCUGCUCUAAUGGAUAGAAUAAGGAGCUGGGAGAAAGGAGACCUGGGUAUUAAUCUCAGCUCUACCACUACAUGGUAGAGCUAUGUAGUGGUAGACUAUCUGGGAGACUCUAGAAUCUUUACCAUUCCCUCUACUAUUCCUAGCUCCCUUUUCUUUCAUAGUCAACAAGUGCUUUUUGAACAAUUAUUGAGGUAAAUAACAUACCCUAAAAGUUAGUACUGAUUCCCAUUAUCAUGCUCUGUUGUUCCCUGGAUGCUCUUUUGAGGAAUUUACUUGGUUAAUACAGUUAAUAGUAUAAUACUUAUAAUAACAAUUUUGAGAAUUAUCAGCAUGAGACAAUUUAUUUGCAUAAUAGCUUUUUGUUAUUAUCCAGAAUACAUUUAGUUCUGGAUUUUGUUUGAUAUUGUGAAUGCAAACUAUUUUUUUGUGUUAGCCUAAAUAAAAUGAAAUACAGUUAUGGAAAUAUUUCUGCUGCAAGAAAAGAAUUACAUACAACUAGUAUACAUAUUUAGAGGUGCUGUAGUCUUCUAGACUGUAAAGGCAGAUGGCCGUGAGUGGAAAUCUGAGUGUAUAGGAUGUGUUUCGUGUUCCCACUGCAUAUGCAUUAUUACCCUUGUCUGAGUGGUUGUUUAAACUGACAUCUGUAAAACUAAUCUGUAAAGUGAGAUCUGGGUUCUGACCUAUCUCUUACAGUCCAUAAUGUUGUGAUUCUAAGAAUAUUUCAUUCCUUACUGCUUUCUGCCCUCCAUUCUGACCAAUGCUGCAACCACAAAUAAAAACAUUACUUACCCUAUGAGAAAGACUAGACCUUAUACUCAUUUUAUCUUAACAGUUUAUUAUAACUCAUUUUGACCACUCCUCCCUCAAAAAAAAUUGUCCCUAGAAAACUAGAGUGAUCAUAGGGAUCAGAUGACAUGUUACUGGGUGAAGCCAGGAAGCUACCAUAUACAUAGAAAAGUUAGUUGCCAAAUAUGGUGUGGGAAUUUGGGAGGAAUUUAUCUGCUCAAAAACUCUCACCUACUUACUAGAUAUAGUGUUUGUAAUGUUAGCCUUGGAGAUUCUACCUUAAAAAUAUCAUUGAGAAAGCUCAGAGAACUCCCAGGUAAACACACAGGUAGCCCCUUCUAAAAUGCAAAUGCCCUUUGAAGGCCAGCUUUAUUAAUCUUGCCAUUAACCCCAUAGUUAAUCAUAUGCAUUUCUCACAGUGACCUGAAAACAGGCAUUCCUUCUCUAAAUGUGUGCUGAAUGCUGGUUAUAAACCAGUUACUACACUAAGCCCUGAUGAUACAAAUAUGAAAAGUCCUGUUUCCAGGGAAUUUACUUUCUAAUGAGGAACCAAGUGCUCAAAAGCAGUCAUAAAGUUCAUGGCAAAAUAACCCACAUAAUUAACUGCUUUGUUACAAAAACUUGGAAAUAUAGAUAAAAUAUUUAUUUUGGAAAUAUAUGUUACAGGUGAAAAGCAAGAAUUAAAACUAGUUAUCUGAAUGUAAAAGGAAUCAACGGCUAAAUCAAGCUUAAAGUCUUCCUGUCCAAGGGAUAUGAAAGGUACCUCAACCUUUGGUUUUGGUUUUGGUUUUGGUUUUGUUUUUUUGGUCAACAUGAAUUAUAGCUAGGGGAAGAGAUAAACAGGGGGUUAGGUUGUAGAUUAUAUGCAUGACAGAUUGCUGGAAUUGGGCUCCAUUCACAAAGGAGGGAGCAGGAAAGGGUUUCUCUUGACUGGACCACAAAUAUAAAAUCUCAUGCCCUCUCAUUAUCUUGAUAAGCCCUAUAGGUCCAUAAAAGAAAUAAAAUGCCAAAACAUACCAUGAGGACACUUUCACAAUCCAGGGCACACACAUGACUCCCGCAAUAGGAAACCACACUGAAGACAUUCUCACAAUUUAAAACAAGUUGUAAACUACAGGAAACAGUUGGCAUCCCAGGAGAGUUGUUGCCUGAGGAACUAGAUGGUGGUAUGUUAUUCUGGCAUAUAGGGAACAGAAUAAGACAUGAGGGUAGGAAGAGGUUUUUAAAAGCAAAGUUAGGCAUUCAAUGAUGACUUCAUAAAUGUGCCUGGGCUGGCCUUUAAUGGAAGGCUUUAAUUUAGGGAACUUAAAGAAUUUCAUAAUAUUGGAGUAUAAACUGCUGGAAAUAAGGAUGCUAUUUAAUAGACUCUCUUAGAUUUUUCAUAAAAUGCUAAUAGAAUCCCAAAGGAAGUGUGUAUUCUAAAAUGUUAUUGUGUAUGUUAUAAAAGCUUUGUAAAAUAAAGUGAUGUUAAGCUACUAUUGUAAAGUUAAAAAUUUUUUCAGUCAUCUGUAAUCUCAUUACCCAAGUAAAACUGUUUUCAUUUUUCCAUUA